CAAAGCACCUGGAGCAUAUAGCCUUGCAGAACUUCUACUUGCCUGCCUCCCUGCCUCUGGCCAUGGCCUGCCGGUGCCUCAGCUUCCUUCUGAUGGGGACCUUCCUGUCAGUUUCCCAGACAGUCCUGGCCCAGCUGGAUGCACUGCUGGUCUUCCCAGGCCAAGUGGCUCAACUCUCCUGCACGCUCAGCCCCCAGCACGUCACCAUCAGGGACUACGGUGUGUCCUGGUACCAGCAGCGGGCAGGCAGUGCCCCUCGAUAUCUCCUCUACUACCGCUCGGAGGAGGAUCACCACCGGCCUGCUGACAUCCCCGAUCGAUUCUCGGCAGCCAAGGAUGAGGCCCACAAUGCCUGUGUCCUCACCAUUAGUCCCGUGCAGCCUGAAGACGACGCGGAUUACUACUGCUCUGUUGGCUACGGCUUUAGUCCCUAGGGGUGGGGUGUGAGAUGGGUGCCUCCCCUCUGCCUCCCAUUUCUGCCCCUGACCUUGGGUCCCUUUUAAACUUUCUCUGAGCCUUGCUUCCCCUCUGUAAAAUGGGUUAAUAAUAUUCAACAUGUCAACAACA